GAUGGGUGGGAACAGGGUGGGUGGUGUUUGUGGGAUUGACAAUGAGCUGGUGUUGUGCAGGGCAGGCCUUACCUCCUUCUCACCCCAACUGAGGGAGGGUUGACUGUUUCUACACACCCCCUUGUUUUUCACACCCGGGACUUGGCCCUAAGGGACUUUCCCAAAGGCACACAGCUGGUGGGGCCUGAGGGAGGAUGACGGAGGUGUGGGCCCCCUCACACCCCUGUUGAGUCCUGCUGGCAAGGCUCCUCCCUAUGGGGGCACCAGGAGAGAAACAACUGUGAGGCUCAGUUUGUUUGGUUUGGAGGCCUAAUACCUUGAGGCCCUGCGCCUCCAGGAGGUCUGGCUCUGCCACUGGCUCACUGUGGGUGUGACCGGGACCGGGGCCUAGCUUUGCCCUAUGCCUCAGUUUCCUCAGUUGCACAAAGGAGUUAAGUUCUGGGUUGGCUCAUGCUUUUUUGCCUCCCAGGGCAAUGGCGCACCCGGGGAGAGGGGUCAUCUGCAGUUGCAGUCACAGAUGGGAAAAUGAGGCCCAGAGAUGAGACAGUUUACUCUGGGGCCAGCAGACUCAGUUCUGAGCAUGUGGCCAGCAGCCAGGAGAGGAGACUGCAGGGGGAAAUGCCAGCAAAGCCCAGCCUUUUUGCAUCUCCAGUUUUCUUUAACCUGCCCUCCAGCCCUCCUUUGCCUGAGUUCACAACUCAACCCCAGCUGCGUGUAUCCUGACGCAAGGCCCCCUUCCCUCCACCCAGCAAUUAUGGCUGGUCACAAAAGCUGGACCGUGACCAGACAAAGGGACAGGGAUGAAAGUGCUGGUUGUCAUGGCAACCUGGUGGGGUUGCUGGGACCCAGGGGAGGGGCUGGCUAUGUGCCUGAGCCCAGGCAUCAGGACGAGACCUGUGAGCAUGAGCCAGGGCAGCCUGACGGCCCACAGGGACCCCCCUCCUGCUCUGGGCCCGCCAAAGCCGGGCAUACAAUGGCAACCUCAGCCCCUCCAUGGGCAGCACCUGCUCCCUGGGCCUCCCCCAGUGGCCCCAUUAUCCUGCACCUGCUGACCACCGCCCCCCCAACCUGCUUCCCAGCCCAAGCUCCCUCCCCAGGGCAGGCCCUGCCCAUCCUCAGGCCCACCUGCCUUCUCUGAGAGCCAGCCAAGAGGGCUGGGGAACCAGGAGGGAUAGCAGGGAAGGCCCUGGGCAGGGACCGAGGGUCCAGCUGCCAAGCCAGCUCUGCCUGGCCAGCAGUGUGUGUGCCUGCAAAACAAGGCUUUGCUCCAGGACCUCAGUCUGCUCACCUGAAAACUGGGAGCAUCCAAUCCUGCCUUCAGGGUCUGCAAGGGCCAGUUUCUCUCUGCUUGGAGGGAGGGCUGAGGCCAGGUUGGGAAGAGAACAGACGGGGGUAUCUUGGGUCAUAUUUUCAGGGCCGCAUCUGUUGGACCACAUGGAGACCUGAGUCCUUACUGUACACUUCAGAGUCACUGCUUAGGUUUGGAGAUGACAUUUUCCAGAGGCCUCCAAGGAUACAGAGGAAGUGGGCAGGAGACCCAGUAUUGCCACGCUUUUUUUUUUUUUUUUUGAGAUGGAGUCUCUCUCUGUCACCCAAGCUGGAGCACAGUGCCACGAUCUCGGCUCACUGGAACCUCUGUCUCCUGGGUUCAGGCAGUUCUCCUGCCUCAGCCUCCCAUGUAGCUGGGACUACAGGGAUGUGCCACCACGUCUGGCUAAUUUUCGUAUUUGUUUUGUUUUGUUUUGUUUUUUGAGACGGAAUCUUGUUCUGUCGCCCAGGCUGGAGUGCAGUGGUGCGAUCUCGGCUCACUGCAAGCUCCGCCUCCCAGGUUCACACCAUUCUCUUGCCUCAGCCUCCCGAGUAGCUGGGACUACAGGCGCCCACCACCACACCUGGCUAAUUUUUUGUAUUUUUAGUAGAGACGGGGUUUUACUGUGUUAGCCAGGAUGGUCUCGAUCUCCUGACCUCGUGAUCUGCCCGCCUCAGCCUCCCAAAGUGCUGGGAUUACAAGUGUGAGCCAGCAUGCCCAGCCUAAUUUUUGUAUUUUUUAGUAGAGACAGGGUUUCACCAUGUUGCCCACUGGUCUUGAACUCCCGAACUCAAAUGAUCCGCCCACCUCGGCCUCCCAAAGUGCUGGGAUUACAGGCAUGAGCCACCACGCCUCGCCAGUGCCAGGCUCUUGAGUGGCCUAUCAGGAGUACUGGGGAAAGAGAAAGACAGUGGGGUGGGUACUCUGCAGGAGGAGAGUGCUCCACAGGGGGCAGCUGGAGGAUGGCUGGGGGCCCUGUUGAUGGACAGUCCAGUUCUUCCAUAAACAGGGAAACUGAGACUCUAGCAACUAUCAGUGUCUGGCGCAAAAGGUAGGCCUGCCUGCCAGCUCCCUGAUGCCCCACCUCAGGAUGGUGGAGUGGAGGAGGGACAAAGAGUGAGAGGAGUGUGAGGCCAGGUAGAUGCCCCUCCUCCUCCUGUAAAGGGAAGUGGGAUUCUCAUGGCAAUGGGUCUUUGUCUCAUGGUCUUUUCCUUGUGGCUCCCUAUAUCCUGCAGGACAGCCCCAGGUUCCUGUCCCACUCUGCCAUGACUUUGGGUGAGGCCCCUCCUUUCUUGCCACCUCAGUUUGCAGACCCAGAGUAUGGGAGCAGAUUGCCAAGGAAGUUGUCAGCUCUAACUGCCACCCUAGCUGUUUGAAUGUCCCUAGGCCAAAGCAGGCAGGCCAUUUGCAAGGGGUGAUGGGGAGGAGGGCUGCCCCACCUCUUUGGGAGUGAGGGAUUCCAUCUCUUUGGAACAAACCCUUCCUUACUGACCUGCUGGGAGUUUUUUACACAUUCGCUCCUGGAGGUCUGGCAAGGGCAGUGCUUUUGCCAGGAAUGGAAGUAUUUGGGGCAGGAAAAGUCUUGGUGUCCCUCACACCACUCUGUACUGAUGACCCCACCGUGACACUGGGUAAGGUUUCUGUUCCUCAUUGUGCAGAAGAAAAACUGAGGCCUAACAAAGGAAGGGACUUGCCCGGUGAGUCAUCAGAAUAAUCCAGGCCUCCUGCCCCGUCCAGAGCCCUUUCUAGGGGUGGAUGAAAGGUCAGGCUGGCAGUCUGGUCCCCAAAGUGGCCAGCCUUGGGGGAUGAGUGGAUGGGAGGGCUCAGCUAAGCCUCAGCAAACCCAGGCUCCCUGGAAGGUGGGAGUGGGGGCACUUGGUGGGUCACAGGGCCAAGUUGAUGAAGUCACCCACUCUGCCAAGAUAUUACUCCAGCUGACGCUCACCAAACUCCUUGGGACUGAGGAAAAAUCAGAGGUGCUCAGAGCCUAAUUAUAAUAAACAGUUUCCUGUGCAGCUCCUGGAGCCCCCCUGGGAAAUGUCCUGUGGAAGAUGUCUUUGUCUCAGAGCCUGCCAUCUGGCGCUUUGGCCCAGGAAGGUGGGGACCAACAGGCAUCCCCCCCUUGGGCCGCUGCUCCUGGAGCGCAGAGCCUCAGCAUCCUGCACCCUCAGAUGGAGGUCAGAGAAAAAUAGGCUGGGGGAGAGGAGGUGAGGGUGGGAUCAUGUGGGGUCAUGUGCAACUGGGCUGGUGUCAACAGCCACUAUCUUUGAGGUGAUGGCCCCGAUGUGGGUUGCUCUAUCUUCCAGUCAUUUCUAUGGGUCUUUCCUGGACUGACGCAUGGGCAGGGCUGCUGAGAAAAGCUGUGCCUCUGCCCCAGCACCCCCUGACCCCAUCCAUCAAGUCCACCCUCCAGUUGGGAGAAACAGCAGUGACCAUCACAUGGUAGGGAGUGAGUCAUCUACCAAGUGGUACUGACCAUGGUCCUCUGGGGCCCUGAGGAGAGUGUGUGUUCUGUUGGCCAAGGCACUCAGGGAGUGUGUCCUGAGAAGUAGCCCAAGAUGGCAUGGAAGAUCAUAGAAAAACAAAGAGGGAAGAGGCUCCGGCAGGGAGGCUGCACAGGAGUAAAGGUGGGCAGGGGAUUAGGUGGGGGCUGUGAUGGAUGAAGAUUGUCUGUUCAUGGGCCAGUGGUCUUCAGUCCACCAGCCCCGGAGAAACUCUGUUCUACUCCUUGCUUGAGCUCUGGGCUUUCAAGGUCUUGUCUGUCAAGGUGAUCAUGUGGAUCAAAGGAGAAUUAAAUUUUCUCCAUUUUUAUUCAUCAAAGAAAUGAUUAUGCUGGUCAGAACUGCUGAGGGCAGCUGAGCAAUGGCAGGGAGGCUUAUGUCGGGGAGGCCUGGGGAGGCAGUGAAUCGUAGACCUCACCCAUUCCCUUCUCUGACACCCCCCGCCCCCGAUGCCUGCAACUCACUUUCUUGUGGCAUAGCUCAGAGCUCCAGGCCUAGAAAAUCAGAGGAAGAUCCUGGGGGCCCAAGAGGGAGGCUGGGGACAGGUGGGGAGCGGGUAGCUCAGCCACUCAGUCUGGAUGCCUGUCACCUUCCGUUCUGGCUGGCCAGCCACAUGAAGGGCCCAUUCUGCUGCCCAUUCACAAGGGGCUUUCAUCUCUGCAGCCAGUGAAGCAUUGCUCCCAUCUCAGCCAGCAAGGAGACACAGGGGAGGGGGUGUGCAGACUUGCCAUGACCUCAGACUCCAUGCUGGAAAGGCAUGGCCCUGGGCCAGGGCAUCCUAAGCAGCCCAUCUGCCCCAAUCCCCCAGCUUCCAGGCCACCAGAGUCCUCAGCAAGGGGGAUCUGAGUAAGAGAUGGGCAGUGACUCCCCAACUCUUGUAGAAACCUAGUCCUCCCAUUUCAACAAGGGUAAGGCUGACCUCUCUUCCAGCUUAUUCAGGGCAAAAGAUGGCCCUCCCAUCACAAGAGGGGCAGGAGUCCAGUGGGUCAUGGCUCAGCCCCCUGCUCCUUUCCCAGGGAGCAAGGUAAGUAUGGUGGCCUUCAGGACAGGGCAGGAAGACCAAAGCCUGAACCCUUGCGCAGCCAUGGGAGAAGACAGCACAUUAGAGGGUAGCCCCUGAGACCCAGGAGAACAGGGACUGACUCACGGUGUCCUUCCAGGGAGGAGGGAGGCAGUCAUAUCCACAGCCCGCCCUUGAAGAGGGGCGAAGUGGAGCUGGCAGGGCUGCUGGUAAAAGCAGCACCCCCGACCCCCACCCCUCAAGUCCAUUCUCCAGUUGGGAGAAACAGCAGUGACCAUCACAUGUGAUCACUGAGUACCUGUGUGAAUGCCAACAAGAAAAAUAAAACCACAGUUUGGAUUCAGGAAAGGUUGCACCACCAUCAGGUCUUGAAGGGAGCUUCGGCUGGGGCAUCUCCCUGAGAAGCAGCAUGGAGCAGCCUAACAGUAAAGGCUAUAGCCUGGGAAGGACCCCUCAGGGCCCAGAGUGCAGCAGUGCUCCUGCAGUCCAAGUGGGGACCCACAGGGGCCUAGAGUAUAACCCGGGGAAGAUUCUUCCAGGAUCAGACUAUGGGUUGGGAAAUCCUCCAGCCCUUGACCCCAAGCUCCCACAUUUACCCCUGCCCCCGGCCCCACCCACACUCUCAGACUUGGGGCAGCCACGGAAGUCACCCCUGACAGGCACUGAUAAGAAGUACCCGCUGAUGAAGCAGCGUGGGUUCUACUCCGACAUCCUCAGCCCUGGAACCUUAGAUCAACUUGGGGAGGUAUGUCGUGGCCCCCGAAUGAGCCAGAACCUCCUGCGGCAGGCUGACCUUGACAAGUUCACCCCAAGAGUCGGAAGCUUUGAGGUUCCUGAAGACUUCCAGGAGCGCAUGGAGCAGCAGUGCAUCGGGUCCACCACCCGGCUGCUCGCCCAGACUGACUUCCCACUGCAGGCCUACGAGCCCAAGAUGCAGGUGCCUUUCCAGGUGCUGCCAGGCCAGCAUCCUCGCAAGAUUGAGAUCGAGAGGAGGAAACAGCAGUACCUGAGCCUGGACAUUGAGCAGUUGCUGUUCAGCCAGGGCAUCGACUCCAACAAGCUCAUGCCCAGGCACCUGGACCACCAGCACCCCCAAACCAUCGAACAGGGCCAUGACCCAAUCUUCCCCAUCUACCUCCCACUGAAGGUAUUUGACAAUGAGGACUUUGACUGCCGGACUCCCAGAGAGUGGAUCAACAUGGGCUUGGAGCCAGGGUCUCUGGACAGGAAACCUGUCCCGGGAAAAGCCCUCUUGCCCACUGAUGACUUCCUGGGGCAUGAGGACCCCAAGAGUCAGAAGCUGAAGUACAAAUGGUGCGAGGUCGGCGUCCUGGACUACGACGAGGAGAAGAAGCUAUACCUGGUACACAAGACAGACGAGAAAGGCCUGGUGCGAGAUGAGAUGGGGAGGCCCAUCCUGAAUGCAGGGGUCACCACUGAAGGAAGGCCACCCCUUCAGGUCUGUCAGUACUGGGUGCCACGGAUCCAGCUUCUCUUCUGCGCUGAGGACCCUUGCAUGUUCGCACAACGUGUGGUCCAGGCCAACGCCCUGCGCAAGAACACGGAAGCACUGCUGCUCUACAACUUGUAUGUGGACUGCAUGCCCUCUGACGGCCAGCAUGUCAUCAGUGAACAGAGCCUGAGCAAGAUCAAGCAGUGGGCCCUGAGCACGCCUCGGAUGCGCAAAGGCCCCUCGGUUCUAGAGCACCUCAGCAGUCUUGCCAGAGAAGUGAGCCUGGACUAUGAGCGCAGCAUGAACAAGAUCAACUUUGACCACGUUGUCUCUUCCAAGCCCGAGACCUUCUCCUACGUCACCCUCCCCAAGAAGGAGGAGGAGCAGGUGCCUGAGCGAGGGCUGGUGAGUGUCCCCAAGUACCACUUCUGGGAGCAGAAGGAGGACUUCACUUUCGUGUCCCUGCUCACACGGCCAGAGGUCAUCACGGCCCUCAGCAAGGUGAGGGCCGAGUGCAACAAGGUGACCGCCAUGUCCCUGUUCCACUCGAGCCUCUCCAAGUACAGCCACCUGGAGGAAUUUGAGCAGAUCCAGUCACAGACCUUCUCCCAGGUGCAGAUGUUCCUCAAGGACAGCUGGAUCAGCUCGCUAAAGGUGGCCAUGCGCAGCAGCCUGCGCGACAUGAGCAAGGGCUGGUACAACCUCUACGAGACCAACUGGGAGGUGUACCUCAUGUCCAAGCUGCGCAAGCUGAUGGAGCUGGUGAAGUACAUGCUGCAGGACACACUGCGCUUCCUGGUGCAGGACUCACUUGCCAGCUUCUCACAGUUCAUCAGCGACACCUGUUGCAGCGUGCUCAACUGCACCGAUGACAUGGUCUGGGGUGACGACUUAAUUAACAGCCCCUACAGGCCCCGGAAGAAUCCCCUGUUCAUCAUGGACCUGGUGCUGGACAGCUCUGGGGUGCACUAUAGCACCCCACUGGAGCAGUUUGAGGCAUCUCUGCUGAACCUCUUCGACAAGGGCAUCCUGGCCACCCAUGCCGUGCCCCAGCUGGAGAAGCUGGUGAUGGAGGACAUCUUCAUCAGCGGUGACCCCCUGCUGGAGUCCGUGGGCCUUCAUGAGCCACUGGUGGAAGAGCUACGGGCCACCAUUGCCAGUGCCGUGUCCAAGGCCAUGAUCCCACUGCAGGCCUACGCCAAGGAGUACCGAAAGUACCUGGAGCUGAACAACAAUGACAUUGCCUCCUUUCUCAAAACCUACCAGACGCAGGGCCUGUUGGCCCAGGAGGUGCGGGAGGUAGUGCUCACCCACCUGCGGGAGAAGGAGAUCCUGGACAGCUCGCUGCCCAGCAGCAUCAUCAUUGGGCCUUUCUACAUCAACACCGACAAUGUCAAGCAGAGCCUGUCCAAGAAACGCAAGGCCCUGGCCACUUCCGUGCUGGACAUCCUUGCCAAGAACCUGCAUAAGGAGGUGGAUAGCAUCUGCGAGGAGUUCCGCAGCAUCAGCCGCAAGAUCUAUGAGAAGCCCAACAGCAUUGAGGAGCUGGCUGAGCUGCGAGAGUGGAUGAAGGGCAUCCCGGAGAGGCUGGUGGGCCUGGAGGAGCGGAUUGUGAAGGUCAUGGAUGACUACCAGGUCAUGGAUGAAUUCCUCUACAACCUCAGCUCAGAUGACUUCAAUGACAAAUGGAUUGCCAGCAACUGGCCUUCUAAGAUCCUUGGGCAGAUAGAGCUGGUGCAGCAGCAGCAUGUGGAGGAUGAGGAGAAGUUCCGCAAAAUCCAGAUCAUGGAUCAGAACAACUUCCAAGAGAAGCUGGAAGGGCUGCAGCUGGUAGUAGCUGGCUUCUCCAUCCAUGUGGAGAUUUCACGUGCACACGAGAUCGCCAACGAGGUGCGGCGUGUCAAGAAGCAGCUGAAGGACUGCCAGCAGCUGGCCAUGCUCUACAACAACCGCGAGCGCAUCUUCAGCUUGCCCAUCACCAAUUAUGACAAGCUCUCCAGGAUGGUGAAGGAGUUCCAACCCUACCUGGACCUUUGGACCACAGCGUCUGACUGGCUGCGCUGGUCGGAGAGCUGGAUGAAUGACCCCCUCUCUGCCAUCGAUGCUGAGCAGCUGGAGAAGAACGUGGUUGAAGCCUUCAAGACCAUGCACAAGUGCGUGAAGCAGUUUAAGGACAUGCCAGCCUGCCAGGAAGUGGCCUUGGACAUCCGGGCCCGCAUCGAGGAGUUCAAACCAUACAUCCCACUGAUCCAGGGGCUGCGCAACCCUGGCAUGCGGAUCCGGCACUGGGAGACACUGUCCAACCAGAUCAACAUCAAUGUCAGGCCCAAGGCCAACCUGACCUUUGCUCGCUGCCUGGAGAUGAACCUGCAGGACCAUAUCGAGAGCAUCAGCAAGGUGGCUGAGGUGGCUGGCAAGGAGUACGCCAUCGAGCAGGCACUGGACAAGAUGGAGAAGGAGUGGUCGACCAUCCUGUUCAAUGUACUGCCCUACAAGGCGACAGACACCUACAUCCUGAAGAGCCCGGACGAGGCCUCACAGCUGCUGGACGACCACAUCGUCAUGACCCAGAAUAUGUCAUUUUCACCCUACAAGAAGCCCUUUGAGCAGCGCAUCAACUCCUGGGAGAACAAACUGAAGCUGACCCAGGAGGUUCUGGAGGAGUGGCUGAACUGUCAGCGGUCCUGGCUCUACCUGGAGCCCAUCUUUAGCUCUGAGGACAUCAACCAGCAGCUGCCUGUGGAGAGCAAGCGCUACCAGACCAUGGAGCGGAUCUGGAAGAAGAUCAUGAAGAAUGCCUACGAGAACCGGGAGGUGAUCAAUGUGUGUUCCGACCUGAGAAUGCUGGACAGCCUGCGGGACUGCAACAAGAUUCUGGACCUGGUGCAGAAGGGCCUCAGCGAGUAUCUGGAGACCAAGAGGAGCGCCUUCCCCAGAUUCUACUUCCUGUCAGAUGAUGAACUACUAGAGAUCUUGUCGCAGACAAAGGACCCCACGGCCGUGCAGCCACACCUGCGCAAGUGCUUCGAGAACAUCGCUCGGCUGCUAUUCCAGGAGGACCUGGAGAUCACGCACAUGUACUCAGCCGAGGGGGAGGAGGUACAGUUGUGCUUCUCCAUCUACCCCUCCAGCAACGUGGAGGACUGGCUGCGGGAGGUGGAGCGCAGCAUGAAGGCCAGUGUGCACGACAUCAUUGAGAAGGCCAUCAGGGCCUACCCCACGAUGCCCAGGACCCAGUGGGUUCUGAACUGGCCUGGCCAGGUGACCAUCGCUGGGUGCCAGACCUACUGGACCAUGGAGGUGGCAGAGGCUCUGGAGGCCGGCAACCUCAGAAGCCAACUGUUCCCCCAGCUCUGCCAGCAGCUCAGUGAUCUGGUGGCCCUUGUGCGGGGGAAGCUGUCCCGCAUGCAGCGGGCAGUGCUGUCAGCGCUAAUCGUCAUUGAGGUCCAUGCCAAGGACGUGGUGAGCAAGCUAAUCCAGGAGAACGUGGUCAGCGUGAAUGACUUCCAGUGGAUCUCACAGCUGAGGUACUACUGGACAAAUAAUGACCUGUAUAUCCGUGCUGUGAAUGCUGAGUUCAUCUAUGGCUAUGAGUACCUGGGCAACAGUGGGAGGCUGGUGAUCACGCCCCUCACCGACAGGUGCUACCUGACACUGACCGGAGCUCUGCACCUCAAGUUUGGGGGUGCCCCAGCUGGCCCAGCUGGCACAGGCAAAACUGAGACCACCAAAGACCUGGGUAAGGCCUUGGCCAUACAGACCGUUGUGUUCAACUGCUCUGACCAGCUCGACUUCAUGGCCAUGGGCAAGUUCUUCAAGGGCCUGGCCAGUGCUGGGGCCUGGGCCUGCUUCGACGAGUUCAAUCGCAUCGACAUCGAGGUGCUGUCUGUGGUGGCGCAGCAGAUCACCACCAUCCAGAAGGCGCAGCAGCAGCGGGUGGAACGCUUCAUGUUUGAGGGUGUGGAGAUCCCACUGGUGCCAUCCUGCGCAGUGUUUAUCACCAUGAACCCGGGCUACGCUGGCCGCACGGAGCUGCCUGACAAUCUGAAGGCGCUCUUCCGACCCGUGGCCAUGAUGGUUCCAGAUUACGCCAUGAUCACUGAGAUCUCCCUCUAUUCCUUUGGCUUUAAUGAGGCCAGUGUGCUGGCUAAGAAGAUCACAACCACCUUCAAGCUGUCUUCUGAGCAGCUCAGCUCCCAGGAUCACUAUGACUUCGGGAUGAGAGCCGUGAAAACUGUGAUCUCGGCUGCUGGGAACCUCAAGCGAGAAAACCCCAGCAUGAAUGAGGAGCUGAUCUGCCUCCGGGCCAUCCGUGAUGUGAACGUGCCCAAGUUCCUGCAGGAGGACCUCAAGCUCUUCUCUGGCAUCGUGUCCGACCUGUUUCCCACCAUCAAGGAGGAGGACACGGACUACGGCAUCCUGGAUGAGGCCAUCCGCGAGGCCUGCAGGAACAGCAACCUCAAGGAUGUGGAGGGCUUCCUGACAAAGUGCAUCCAGCUCUACGAGACCACGGUGGUACGACACGGCCUCAUGCUCGUCGGGCCCACAGGCUCCGGCAAGAGUACUUGUUACAGAGUCCUGGCAGCUGCCAUGACGUCACUGAAAGGGCAGCCAUCCAUCAGUGGUGGCAUGUACGAGGCUGUCAACUACUACGUGCUCAACCCCAAGUCCAUCACGAUGGGCCAGCUGUACGGGGAGUUUGACCUCCUCACCCAUGAGUGGAGAAGGUUCCGGAGCCUAAGGCUGGACCAAGCACAGCAUCUUCAUCAGCCCUACCAGCCCCUUCCCUGGACAGACGGGAUAUUCUCCUCGUUCAUCCGGGCGGGGGCCAUCACCUCCGACACCAACAAGAAGUGGUACAUGUUCGAUGGGCCGGUGGAUGCCAUCUGGAUUGAGAACAUGAACACGGUGCUGGAUGACAACAAGAAGCUGUGCCUCAGCUCUGGGGAGAUCAUCAAGCUCACAGAGGCAAUGACCAUGAUGUUCGAGGUGCAAGACCUGGCGGUGGCUUCACCAGCUACAGUCUCCCGCUGUGGCAUGGUGUACCUGGAGCCCAGCAUCCUGGGGCUCAUGCCCUUCAUCGAGUGCUGGCUGAGGAAGCUGCCUCCCUUGCUGAAGCCCUAUGAGGAGCAUUUCAAGGCCCUCUUUGUCAGCUUCCUGGAGGAAUCCAUCUCCUUCGUUCGGUCCUCAGUGAAGGAGGUGAUCGCCUCAACCAACUGCAACCUGACCAUGAGCCUCCUCAAGCUGCUGGACUGCUUCUUCAAGCCCUUUCUGCCUAGAGAGGGCCUCAAGAAAAUACCCUCUGAAAAGCUGAGUCGCAUCGUAGAGUUGAUCGAGCCCUGGUUCAUCUUCUCCCUGAUCUGGAGCGUGGGUGCCACUGGGGACAGCAGUGGCCGCACCAGUUUCAGCCACUGGCUAAGGCUCAAGAUGGAGAACGAACAGCUGACUCUGCUUUUCCCAGAAGAGGGGCUGGUGUUCGAUUACAGGCUGGAGGACGCGGGCAUCAGUGGCACCAACGACAGUGAGGAUGAAGAGGAGGAAUACAAGCAGGUUGCCUGGGUGAAGUGGAUGGACUCCUCAGCUCCAUUCACCAUGGUACCAGACACCAACUACUGCAACAUCAUUGUGCCCACCAUGGACACCGUGCAGAUGUCCCAUUUACUGGACAUGCUGCUCACCAACAAGAAGCCCGUGCUGUGCAUUGGGCCAACAGGCACGGGGAAGACGCUCACCAUCUCUGACAAGCUCCUCAAGAACCUGGCACUGGAUUACAUCAGCCACUUCCUCACCUUCUCAGCCCGCACUUCAGCCAACCAGACCCAGGACUUCAUUGACAGCAAGCUGGACAAGAGGCGGAAGGGUGUGUUUGGACCACCUCUGGGGCGCAACUUUAUCUUCUUCAUCGAUGACCUGAACAUGCCGGCCCUGGAGACCUACGGUGCACAGCCACCCAUCGAGCUGUUGCGCCAGUGGAUGGACCACGGCGGCUGGUACGACCGCAAGAUCAUUGGUGCCUUCAAGAACCUAGUGGACAUCAACUUUGUCUGUGCCAUGGGCCCCCCGGGUGGAGGCAGGAACACCGUCACCCCGCGGCUGAUGCGUCACUUCAACUACCUGUCUUUCGCUGAGAUGGACGAGGUCAGCAAGAAACGCAUCUUCUCCACCAUCCUGGGCAACUGGUUGGAUGGACUCCUUGGAGAAAAAAGCUACCGGGAGCGUGUGCCUGGGGCCCCCCACAUUGCCCACUUCACGGAGCCCCUUGUGGAAGCCACCAUCAUGGUGUAUGCAACCAUCACCUCCCAGCUGCUGCCCACUCCAGCCAAGUCCCACUACACCUUCAACCUGAGGGACCUCUCCAAGGUCUUCCAAGGCAUGCUCAUGGCUGACCCGGCCAAGGUCGAGGACCAAGUGCAGCUGCUGCGACUGUGGUAUCACGAGAACUGCCGCGUGUUCCGGGACCGACUGGUGAAUGAGGAGGACCGCAGCUGGUUCGACCAGCUCCUCAAGCGCUGCAUGGAGCAGUGGGAGGUGACCUUCAACAAGGUCUGCCCCUUCCAGCCCAUUCUUUACGGGGACUUCAUGUCACCAGGCUCCGAUGUCAAGUCCUACGAGCUCAUCACCAGUGAGAGUAAGAUGAUGCAGGUGAUAGAGGAGUACAUAGAGGACUACAACCAGAUCAACACGGCCAAGCUGAAGCUGGUCCUCUUCAUGGACGCCAUGAGCCACAUCUGUCGCAUCAGCCGCACCCUACGCCAGGCGCUGGGCAAUGCACUCCUGCUGGGCGUGGGUGGCAGCGGCCGCAGCUCCCUCACAAGGCUCGCCUCGCACAUGGCCGAGUACGAGUGCUUCCAGAUUGAACUAUCCAAGAACUACGGCAUGUCCGAGUGGCGAGAUGAUGUGAAGAAGGUCCUGCUCAAGGCGGGCCUACAGAACCUACCCAUCACCUUCCUCUUCUCAGACACCCAGAUCAAGAACGAAUCCUUCCUGGAAGAUAUCAACAACGUCCUAAACUCUGGUGACAUUCCCAAUCUGUAUACUGCGGACGAGCAGGACCAGAUCGUCAGCACCAUGCGGCCCUAUAUCCAGGAGCAGGGCCUACAGCCCACCAAGGCCAACCUCAUGGCUGCUUACACAGGGCGUGUGCGCAGCAACAUCCACAUGGUGCUGUGCAUGAGCCCCAUCGGAGAGGUCUUCCGAGCUCGUCUGAGGCAGUUUCCCUCCCUGGUCAACUGCUGUACCAUCGACUGGUUUAACGAGUGGCCGGCAGAAGCCCUGAAGUCUGUGGCCACCGUGUUCCUCAAUGAGAUCCCAGAACUGGAAUCCUCCCAGGAAGAAAUCCAAGGACUGAUCCAGGUCUGUGUGUACAUCCACCAGUCGGUGUCCAAGAAGUGCAUCGAGUACCUGGCAGAGCUGACCCGCCACAACUAUGUGACCCCCAAGAGCUACUUGGAGCUGCUUCAUAUUUUCUCCAUCCUCAUCGGGCAGAAGAAACUGGAGCUGAAAACUGCCAAGAACCGCAUGAAGAGCGGCCUCGACAAGCUGCUGCGCACUUCUGAGGAUGUAGCCAAGAUGCAGGAGGACCUGGAGAGUAUGCACCCCCUGCUGGAGGAGGCUGCCAAGGACACCAUGCUCACCAUGGAGCAGAUCAAGGUGGAUACGGCCAUCGCCGAGGAGACCCGGAAUUCAGUGCAGACAGAGGAGAUCAAAGCCAAUGAGAAGGCCAAGAAGGCACAAGCUAUUGCUGACGAUGCCCAGAAGGACCUGGACGAGGCGUUGCCAGCCCUGGAUGCGGCUCUGGCCAGCCUGCGCAACCUCAACAAGAACGAUGUGACCGAGGUACGUGCCAUGCAGCGGCCACCCCCGGGUGUGAAACUGGUCAUAGAAGCUGUGUGCAUUAUGAAAGGCAUCAAGCCCAAGAAGGUGCCUGGAGAAAAGCCAGGCACCAAGGUGGAUGACUACUGGGAGCCUGGCAAGGGGCUGCUGCAGGACCCGGGCCACUUCCUUGAGAGCCUCUUCAAGUUUGACAAGGACAACAUUGGGGAUGUGGUGAUCAAAGCCAUCCAGCCGUACAUCGAUAAUGAAGAGUUCCAGCCAGCCACCAUUGCCAAGGUGUCCAAGGCUUGCACCUCCAUCUGCCAGUGGGUGCGCGCCAUGCACAAGUACCACUUUGUGGCCAAGGCCGUGGAGCCCAAGCGGCAAGCCCUGCUGGAGGCCCAGGAUGACCUGGGGGUGACACAGAGGAUCCUGGAUGAGGCAAAACAGCGCCUUCGUGAGGUGGAGGACGGCAUCGCCACAAUGCAGGCUAAGUACCGGGAAUGCAUUACCAAGAAGGAGGAGCUGGAGCUGAAGUGUGAGCAGUGUGAGCAGCGGCUGGGCCGAGCUGGCAAGCUCAUCAACGGGCUGUCGGAUGAGAAGGUGCGCUGGCAGGAGACGGUGGAGAACCUGCAGUACAUGCUCAACAACAUCUCCGGCGAUGUCCUGGUGGCCGCUGGCUUUGUGGCCUACCUGGGCCCCUUCACGGGCCAGUACCGCACGGUGCUCUACGACAGCUGGGUCAAGCAGCUCAGGAGCCACAAUGUCCCACACACCUCCGAGCCCACGCUAAUCGGGACGCUGGGGAACCCUGUGAAGAUCCGAUCGUGGCAGAUCGCUGGCCUCCCCAACGACACACUGUCAGUGGAGAACGGGGUCAUCAACCAGUUUUCCCAGCGCUGGACCCACUUCAUUGACCCUCAGAGCCAGGCCAACAAAUGGAUCAAGAACAUGGAGAAGGACAAUGGGCUGGAUGUGUUCAAGUUGAGUGACCGCGACUUCCUGCGCAGCAUGGAGAACGCCAUCCGCUUUGGCAAGCCAUGUCUCCUGGAGAACGUGGGCGAGGAGCUAGACCCAGCCCUGGAGCCAGUGCUGCUCAAGCAGACGUACAAGCAGCAGGGAAACACGGUGCUGAAGCUGGGGGACACGGUGAUCCCCUACCAUGAGGACUUCAGGAUGUACAUCACCACCAAGCUGCCCAACCCACACUACACGCCCGAGAUCUCCACCAAACUCACCCUCAUCAACUUCACCCUGUCGCCCAGUGGCCUAGAGGACCAGCUACUGGGCCAGGUAGUGGCAGAGGAGCGACCCGACCUGGAGGAGGCCAAGAACCAGCUGAUUAUCAGUAAUGCCAAGAUGCGCCAGGAGCUGAAGGACAUUGAGGACCAGAUCCUGUACCGGCUCAGCUCCUCCGAGGGCAACCCUGUAGAUGACAUGGAACUCAUCAAGGUGCUGGAAGCCUCCAAGAUGAAGGCUGCUGAGAUCCAGGCCAAAGUCAGGAUUGCAGAGCAGACGGAGAAGGACAUCGACCUGACGCGCAUGGAGUACAUACCCGUGGCCAUCCGCACCCAGAUCCUCUUCUUCUGUGUGUCCGACCUGGCCAACGUGGACCCCAUGUACCAGUACUCCCUUGAGUGGUUUCUCAACAUCUUCCUCUCGGGCAUCGCCAACUCAGAGAGAGCAGACAACCUGAAGAAGCGCAUCUCCAACAUCAACCGCUACCUGACCUACAGCCUCUACAGCAACGUCUGCCGCAGCCUCUUUGAGAAGCACAAGCUGAUGUUUGCCUUCCUGCUGUGUGUUCGCAUCAUGAUGAACGAGGGCAAAAUCAACCAGAGUGAGUGGCGAUACCUCCUGUCUGGGGGCUCCAUCUCGAUCAUGACUGAGAAUCCGGCACCGGACUGGCUGUCAGACCGGGCUUGGCGAGACAUCCUAGCACUCUCGAACCUGCCAACCUUUUCCUCCUUCUCUUCCGACUUCGUGAAGCACCUCUCAGAAUUCCGGGUCAUCUUCGACAGCCUUGAGCCCCACCGGGAGCCUUUGCCUGGCAUCUGGGACCAGUACCUAGACCAGUUCCAGAAGCUGCUAGUCCUCCGCUGCCUGCGUGGGGACAAGGUUACCAACGCCAUGCAGGACUUUGUGGCCACCAACCUGGAGCCACGCUUCAUUGAACCCCAGACAGCCAAUCUGUCAGUGGUGUUCAAAGACUCCAACUCCACCACACCCCUCAUCUUUGUGCUGUCACCCGGCACAGACCCUGCUGCCGACCUCUACAAGUUUGCCGAAGAAAUGAAGUUCUCCAAAAAGCUCUCUGCCAUCUCCCUGGGCCAGGGGCAGGGCCCUCGGGCAGAAGCCAUGAUGCGCAGCUCCAUAGAGAGGGGCAAAUGGGUCUUCUUCCAGAACUGCCACCUGGCACCAAGCUGGAUGCCAGCCCUAGAACGCCUCAUCGAGCACAUCAACCCCGACAAGGUACACAGGGACUUCCGCCUCUGGCUCACCAGCCUGCCCAGCAACAAGUUCCCAGUGUCCAUCCUGCAGAACGGCUCCAAGAUGACCAUUGAGCCGCCACGCGGUGUCAGGGCCAACCUGCUGAAGUCCUAUAGUAGCCUUGGUGAAGACUUCCUCAACUCCUGCCACAAGGUGAUGGAGUUCAAGUCUCUGCUGCUGUCUCUGUGCUUGUUCCAUGGGAACGCCCUGGAGCGCCGUAAGUUUGGGCCCCUGGGCUUCAACAUCCCCUAUGAGUUCACGGAUGGAGAUCUGCGCAUCUGCAUCAGCCAGCUCAAGAUGUUCCUGGACGAAUAUGAUGACAUCCCCUACAAGGUCCUCAAGUACACGGCAGGGGAGAUCAAUUACGGGGGCCGUGUCACUGAUGACUGGGACCGGCGCUGCAUCAUGAACAUCUUGGAGGACUUCUACAACCCUGACGUGCUCUCCCCUGAGCACAGCUACAGCGCCUCGGGCAUCUACCACCAGAUCCCGCCUACCUACGACCUCCACGGCUACCUCUCCUACAUCAAGAGCCUCCCACUCAAUGAUAUGCCUGAGAUCUUUGGCCUGCAUGACAAUGCCAACAUCACCUUUGCCCAGAACGAGACGUUCGCCCUCCUGGGCACCAUCAUCCAGCUGCAACCCAAAUCAUCUUCUGCAGGCAGCCAGGGCCGGGAGGAGAUAGUGGAGGACGUCACCCAAAACAUUCUGCUCAAGGUGCCUGAGCCUAUCAACUUGCAAUGGGUGAUGGCCAAGUACCCAGUGCUGUAUGAGGAAUCAAUGAACACAGUACUAGUACAAGAGGUCAUUAGGUACAAUCGGCUGCUGCAGGUGAUCACACAGACACUGCAAGACCUACUCAAGGCACUCAAGGGGCUGGUAGUGAUGUCCUCUCAGCUGGAGCUGAUGGCUGCCAGCCUGUACAACAAUACUGUGCCUGAGCUCUGGAGUGCCAAGGCCUACCCAUCGCUCAAGCCUCUGUCAUCAUGGGUCAUGGACCUGCUGCAACGCCUGGACUUUCUGCAGGCCUGGAUCCAAGAUGGCAUCCCAGCUGUCUUCUGGAUCAGUGGAUUCUUCUUCCCCCAGGCUUUCUUAACAGGCACUCUGCAGAAUUUUGCCCGCAAAUUUGUCAUCUCCAUUGACACCAUCUCCUUUGAUUUCAAGGUGAUGUUUGAGGCACCAUCAGAGUUAACACAAAGACCCCAAGUAGGGUGCUAUAUCCAUGGAUUAUUCCUGGAAGGUGCCCGCUGGGAUCCAGAGGCCUUCCAGCUGGCUGAGUCUCAGCCCAAGGAGCUGUACACAGAGAUGGCCGUUAUCUGGCUCUUGCCAACACCCAACCGCAAGGCCCAGGACCAGGACUUUUACCUGUGCCCCAUCUACAAGACACUGACUCGUGCUGGAACACUAUCAACCACAGGACACUCUACCAACUAUGUCAUUGCUGUGGAGAUCCCCACCCAUCAGCCCCAGCGACACUGGAUAAAGCGUGGUGUGGCCCUCAUCUGUGCCCUGGACUACUAGACUCAGACAGAAGGGCUGGGGCCAUUAAAGCUGAAUUUUCUAAGCA